AUGAGGAACCACCUCCUCCUACUGUUCAAGUACAGGGGCCUGGUCCGCAAAGGGAAGAAAAGCAAAAGACGAAAAUGGCUAAAUUCGUGA